GUGUGCGCAAGGAGCGGGCGCGGAGCCGGCGGGCGGGCGGAGGAUAGCGCGGGCGCGGCACCUGCGGGCCCGAGGGUCUGGCUGUCGCAGCGCCGGGCCGCCCCGACUCCGAGCGGCUGCUGAGAUGAGUGCAGUGUCGCAGCCCCAGGCUGCUCCCAGCCCGCUGGAGAAGUCGCCCAGCACGGCGAUCCUGUGCAACACGUGUGGGAAUGUGUGCAAGGGCGAGGUGCUGCGGGUGCAGGACAAGUACUUCCACAUCAAGUGCUUCGUCUGUAAAGCAUGUGGCUGCGACCUGGCCGAGGGCGGCUUCUUCGUGCGGCAGGGCGAGUACAUCUGCACGCUGGACUACCAGAGGCUCUACGGCACCCGCUGCUUCAGCUGCGACCAGUUCAUUGAGGGUGAGGUGGUGUCGGCGCUGGGCAAGACCUACCACCCCGACUGCUUCGUGUGUGCCGUCUGCCGGCUGCCCUUCCCCCCCGGGGACCGAGUGACCUUCAACGGGAAGGAAUGCAUGUGCCAGAAGUGUUCCCUGCCCGUAUCGGUGGGCAGCAGCGCGCACCUGUCCCAGGGCCUCCGAAGUUGUGGGGGCUGCGGCACAGAAAUCAAGAAUGGCCAGGCCCUGGUAGCCUUGGACAAGCACUGGCACUUGGGCUGUUUUAAGUGCAAGAGCUGUGGGAAGCUCCUGAAUGCCGAGUACAUCAGCAAGGAUGGGCUGCCCUACUGCGAAGCUGACUAUCACGCCAAGUUCGGCAUCCGCUGUGACAGCUGUGAGAAAUACAUCACGGGGCGCGUGCUGGAGGCCGGAGAGAAGCACUACCACCCUUCCUGCGCGCUAUGUGUCAGGUGCGGCCAGAUGUUUGCAGAAGGCGAAGAGAUGUAUCUUCAAGGUUCCUCCAUCUGGCAUCCGGCGUGUCGACAAGCAGCCAGAACUGAAGACAGAAACAAGGAAACCAGAACUUCCUCAGAGAGCAUCAUUUCUGUCCCUGCUUCCAGCACCUCAGGGUCUCCGAGCCGUGUGAUUUAUGCCAAGCUUGGUGGUGAGAUCCUGGACUACAGGGACUUGGCAGCCCUUCCUAAAAGUAAGGCCAUCUAUGACAUCGACCGCCCCGACAUGAUCUCCUACUCACCCUACAUCAGCCACUCUGCAGGGGACAGGCAGAGCUACGGCGAGUCCCCUCAGUUGCUCUCGCCAACGCCGACCGAGGGGGAUCAGGAUGACCGGUCCUACAAGCAGUGUCGGACCUCCAGCCCAAGCUCCACUGGGUCGGUUAGCCUCGGGCGCUACACUCCGACCUCACGGUCACCACAGCACUACAGCCGUCCAGCUGGUACUGUGAGUGUGGGUACCAGUAGCUGCCUCUCCCUGUCCCAACACCCAAGCCCUACAUCCGUGUUCAGACAUCAUUACAUCCCCUACUUCCGAGGCAGUGAAAGUGGCCGGAGCACCCCCAGCCUCUCCGUGCUCUCUGACAGCAAGCCGCCCCCCUCCACCUACCAGCAGGCACCUCGCCACUUCCACGUCCCAGACACUGGCGUAAAAGAUAACAUCUAUAGGAAACCCCCUAUCUACAGACAGCAUGGUCCUGUAGCCCAAUCCCAAAUUUCCAAGCUCUCUGGCCUGGUAUCAGUCUUGUCCUUGGUGGUGCAGGAGGCAGGGUACGGCAAAAGACAGACGGGCCCGAGCCCGCCGCCCGCUGCAGCUGCCAGGCGAUCGGAUGGGGAGGAUGGAAGCUUGGACCAGGAUAACAGGAAGCAGAAGAGCAGCUGGCUGAUGCUCAAGGGGGAUGCAGACACAAGGACCAAUUCUCCAGACCUGGACACCCAGUCCUUGUCCCACAGCAGCGGGACCGACAGAGACCCUCUCCAAAGGAUGGCAGGGGACAGCUUUCACUCACGAAACCCGCUGUGUCUAACCAUUCUGAUUGUGCCUUUACUUCUGUCCCGAUGGCAUUGCCUUGUUUCCCGAUUUGCAUGGAAAUGGCAGCGAGGACCCAGACUGCCGGCUGUGCCUGGAUCAGGAUUCCCCUAUUCCAAAUCUGACCCUCUCCCAGGACAUGGAAAGAAUGGCUUGGACCAGCGGAAUGCCAAUCUGGCCCCCUGUGGAGCAGACCCGGAUGCCAGCUGGGGCAUGCGAGAAUACAAGAUCUAUCCGUAUGACUCCCUCAUCGUCACAAACCGAAUUCGCGUGAAACUGCCCAAAGACGUGGACCGGACGAGACUGGAGAGACACUUGUCGCCCGAGGAGUUCCAGGAAGUGUUUGGGAUGAGCAUCGAGGAGUUUGACCGCCUGGCCCUCUGGAAGAGGAAUGACCUUAAGAAGAAAGCCCUUUUGUUCUGACGGCUGCCAGCCUGCCCCACUGGUGUGUGCCGGGCGCCGAGGCCAGGGGCCCCUGGCGAGAACCGCACACACCCCUCCCACACACCUUGCUCUGGCUUCUCUGUGUCCAUGGGGUGGGCGGGAGGGGGUCCCCCAGCAGGUGCGGCCCCUGCACCUGCCGGCGACACUCCUGCCGGUAGUUUAGGGCCGAGACGGCUAGCUUCACGCCACCCUUCCCCGCUGUGGCUUGGUGUCAGGGAGAGGCUGUAGAGUGGCUGUGUCGGGCAUCAGAUGGAGCACACAGGUGGCUGCAGCCCAGCCCACCUUCCCAGCGUUCUCGAGGUGCCCUGGCCCCGGUGCUGGGCACGUGGGGGACAGAGGUGGCCGGGACGUGAGCUGUGAGGCUUGUUGAUGAUGGUUGCUGACACCAUCAUCGGGGGUGGGCACACGGCCCUUCGGAGCCUGGGCAGCCUGGCCUCACAGGCAGACUCGCAGACGGGGCAGUGAGCGUCUGGGACAGUGCCAAGAGUGGGGUGUGUGAUUUUUGCAGGCGUCUGUGAUGGGUCUCUUUAGGGACAAAUGUCAACAAGGGACAAGACAGGGCACCUUCCGCCAGCGCCCCUCCAUGCGCUGCGUUCCUCCUCCAGAUCGACCCCUAGAUGCCUACACAAUAUCUUUAAAGUAACACAGAAGUUUUUAUUUUAUUAAAAAGUAUAGCCUACUUAAACGCGAGAUGACAUAUAUAGAGUUUAAUUUUACGGUCCCUCCGCAGGGGAGCGGCCUCCAGCCUUAUUCUCCACCGCUCGGAUCUGUGUGGUUUCAGUCUGUUCUUGGUGUGGUCCUCAUACACAGAGCUCCCUGUCUAGUUUCUUUUCUUUUUCUUUUUUCUUUUUCUCGUCACACAGGUAACCUUAAAGACAGACCCCUCUAAAGAACGCUUUGUAAAUACAUGUGAGGUAUAGCCACCACUGUUUUCCUUGCUGUUAUUUUUCCAAGUCUUGGGGAGAAAACAUCCUCCUCUGAUGGCCAAAGCCCUGGAAUCAAGGGUUUCCACGUACCCUGCCUAAUACCCGACGUAGCUCUUGAUGCACCGUCCUUGUGCUGUGGCUGGCGGUGUCUCAGCCUGAAACAUAAACCCCACAUGCCCCAGGAGCGAUGUGCUCCCUGAAACAGACAACCACACGCUGUUGGGGAGAGAAGGAUGGAGAUAGGAUGGAGAUAGGAUGGAGAUGUGGCUCUUCUCAUCUUUGAAGCCAGCAGGGCAUCCCGGAGCAGGAGGCUGGCCGGGCUCCCCAAGCGAAGGCGUUGGUGUCUGUCAUUAGGUGUGUGUUAGGGUGCAGCACCGGCCGUCACAGGAUGCUGAUAAGCGCGCUGAGAGGUGGAUGAAACACCAAAGUCUGUUUCCCCGUCCGCAGUGGGUGUUGCCUCUUUGUGUGUGUCCCGAUGUUCCUGCCUGUGAGUCGGCCUUACUCCGUUUCCUUAGCGCCCAUGACACGCCAAGUCCCGUUUCGCACUCGGCUUCUCACCCGCCCAGCUCGGCUAGGGAGGGGGAGUUUUUAGCACCUAAUAUGCUUCCUGCCAUUGCGCAAUCUGAGCCUGAGCAACUGGAAACCCCCAUUUCUCAUUAGUGCAAUGUCAUAUCUGAUCCCAGGAAGCCUGGAAAAUAAAAGACGAUGCAUUAUAA